GGAAACCACAAUCUCACUGAAAAUAUACACUAUUCAGGUAAAAAGCAUACACAUCAUGGCAAGGGAGAAUUCGACCUUCAACUCCGACUUCAUCCUCCUGGGAAUCUUCAAUCACAGCCCCACCCACACCUUCCUCUUCUUUCUGGUCCUGGCCAUCUUUUCAGUGGCCUUCAUGGGAAACUCUGUCAUGGUUCUCCUCAUCUACCUGGACACCCAGCUCCACACCCCCAUGUACCUCCUCCUCAGCCAACUGUCCCUCAUGGACCUCAUGCUCAUCUGCACCACCGUACCCAAGAUGGCCUUCAACUACCUGUCUGGCAGCAAGUCCAUUUCUAUGGCUGGUUGUGCCACACAAAUUUUCUUCUAUACAUCACUGCUUGGCUCUGAGUGCUUUCUUUUGGCUGUUAUGGCUUAUGACCGCUACACUGCCAUUUGCCACCCUCUAAGAUACACCAAUCUCAUGAGCCCUAAAAUUUGUGGACUUAUGACUGCCUUUUCCUGGAUCCUGGGCUCUACGGAUGGAAUUAUUGAUGUUGUAGCAACAUUUUCCUUCUCCUACUGUGGGUCUCGGGAAAUAGCCCACUUCUUCUGUGACUUCCCCUCCCUACUAAUCCUCUCAUGCAGUGACACAUCAAUAUUUGAAAAGAUUCUUUUCAUCUGCUGUAUAGUAAUGAUUGUUUUCCCUGUUGCAAUCAUCAUUGCUUCCUAUGCUCGAGUUAUCCUGGCUGUCAUUCACAUGGGAUCUGGAGAGGGUCGUCGCAAAGCUUUUACUACUUGUUCCUCUCACCUCUUGGUGGUGGGAAUGUACUAUGGAGCAGCUUUGUUCAUGUACAUACGGCCCACAUCUGAUCGCUCCCCAACACAGGACAAGAUGGUGUCUGUAUUCUACACCAUCCUCACUCCCAUGUUGAAUCCCCUCAUCUACAGCCUCCGCAACAAGGAGGUGACCAGAGCAUUCAUGAAGAUCUUAGGAAAGGGCAAGUCUGGAGAGUGAGUUACCUAAUAAACUUCAUGUUUUGCUGUGUGCUAAAUCCUUUUUUUAAAUGGUCCUAUUUUUCCAUUAAGCCUUGAAAAUGGGAUUCAUUGUGUACAUAAAUCUGCAAUGACAUAUUUAUGUGCACCUAUAUAAUUUAUUUCAGAUAAACUAUUAUAACUAUUUAUUAUUUUAUAUUCAUUUCUGCUAUGACCACAAUGUAAGUCAUUUCCAAUAAGAAUAUUAAAGUUUUAAAAAUUAUUUUUAAUUUCCAUAGGUUUUUGGAGAACAGGUAGUGUUUGGUUUUAUGAAUAAGUUCUUUAGUGAUGAUUUCUGAGAUUUUGGUGCACCCAUCACCCAAGCAGUAUUCACUGUACCCAAUGUGUAGUCUUUUAUCACUUGUCAUUCCCCGUAUUUCCCUCAUGUCCCCAAAGUCCAGUGUAUCAUUCUUAUGACUUUUUGUCUCAUAGUUUAGUUUCAACAUAUGAAUGUGAACGUAUGAUGUUUGGUUUUUCAUUCCUGAGUUACUUUACUUAGAAUAAUAGUCUCUAAUUCCAUCCCAGUUGCUGUGAAUGCCAUUAUUUUGUAUUUUUUAUGACUGAGUAGUAUUCCAUGGUAUGUGUGUAUAUAGAUAUAUAUAUAUAUACGUAUAUAUAUACACACACACAUAUAUAUAUAUAACCUUUUCUUUAUCCACUCGUUGAUUGAUGGGCAUUUGGACUGGUUCCAUAUUUUUGCAAUUGCAAAUUGUGCUGCUUUAUACAUGCAUGUGCAGGUAUCUUUUUUGUAUAAUAACUUCUUUUCCUCUGUGUAGUUAGUAGUGGUAUUGCUAGAUCAAAAGGUAGAUCCACUUUUAGUUCUUUAAGGAAUGUUCACACUGUUUUUUACAGUGGUUGAACUAGUUUGCAUUCCCACCAGCAGUGUAAAAGUUCCCUUUUGACCGCAUCCACACCAGCAUCUAUUAUUGUUUGAUUGAUUAUGGCCAUUCUUGCAGAAGUGAGGUGGUAUUGCAUUGUGGUUUUGAUUUGCAUUUCCCUGAUAAUUAGUGAUGUCAAGCAUUUUUCUAGAUGCUUGUUGGCUAUUUAUAUAUAUUUAUAUAUCUCCUUUUGAGAAUUGUCUAUUCAUGUCCUAGGCCCACUUUUUGAUGGGAUCAUUUGUUUUCUUCUUGCUGAUUUGUUUGAGUUCUUUGUAGAUUCUGGAAAUUAAUCCCUUCUCAGAUGUAUAAAUUGUGAAGAUUUUCUCCCACUCUAUGGGUUGUCUAUUUACUCUGCUGACCGUUCCUUUUGCAGUGCAAAAGGUCUUUAGUUUAAUUAGUUCCCAGCUAUUUAUCUUUGUUUUUAUUGCAUUAGUUUUUGGGUUCUUGCUCAUGAAACCCUUGCCUAAGCCAAUGUCUACAAGGAUUUCUCUGAUGUUAUCUUCUGGAAUCUUUAUGUUUUCAGUACUUAGAUUUAAGGUUUUUAUCCAUCUUGAGUUGAUUUUUGUAUAAGGUGAGCGAUGAGGAUCCAGUUUCAUUCUUCUACAUGUGGCCUGUCAGUUAGCCCAGCACCAUUUGUUGAAUAUGGUGUUCUUUCCCCCACUUCAUGUUUUUGUUUGUGUUGUUGAAGAUCAGAUGGCUGUAAGUAUUUUGGUUUAUUUCUGGGUUCUCUAUUCUGUUUUGUCUGUCUAUGUCUCUAUUUUUAUCCAGUACCAUGCUGUUUUGGUGACUAUGGCUUUAUAGUAUAAUUUGAAGUUGGGUAUGUGGUGCCUCCAGAUUUGUUCUUUUUGCUUAUUCUUGCUAUGGCUAUGCAGGACUUUUUUAUUCCAUAUGAAUUUUAGGAUUGUUCUUUCUAGUUCUGUUAAGAAGGAUGGUGAUAUUUUAGUGGGAAUUGCAUUGAAUUUGUAAAUUGCUUUUGGCAGCAUGGUCAUUUUUACAAUAUUGUUUCUACCCAUCCAUGAGUAUGGGAUGUAUUUCCAUUUAUUUGUGUUGUCAAUGAUUUUUUUCAGCAGUGUUUUGUAUUUUUCCUUGUAGAAGUCUUUCACAUCCUUGGUUAGGUAUACUCCUUAAUAUUUUGUGUUGUUGUUGUUAUAUUAUUUGCUUCUGUCAUGAAAGGGUUGAGUUCUUGAUUUGAUUCUCAGCUGGUUGCCAUUAGUAUAUAGCAGAGCUACUGAUUUGUGUACAUUAAUUGUGUGUCCUGAAACUGUUGAAUUUAUUUACCAGUUCUAGGAGCUUUUUAGAUGAGCCGUUAGGGUUUUCUAUGUAUUCCAUCGUAUCAUCAGCAAACAGCGACAGUUUUCCUUUCUCUUUACCAUUUUGGAUGUCCUUUAUUUCUUUCUCUUGUCUGAUUGCUCUAGCUAGGACUUUCAGUAUUAUCUUGAACAGACAUGGUGAAAGUGGACAUCCUUGUCUUGUUCCAGUUCUCAGGGGGAAUGCUUUCCAAUUUUCCCCUUUCAGUAUAAUGUUUGCUGUGGAUUUCUCAUAGAAGGCUUUGAUUACCUUAACGUCACCUCUAUGUCCCUUCGUGUUGAUUUUGCUUAGAAUUUUAAUUGUAAAGGGAUGUGGGAUUUCAUCAAAUGCUUUUUCUCUGUCUAUUGAGAUGAUCAUGUGAUUUUUGUUUUUAAUUCUGUUUAUGUGGUGUAUCAUAUUUAUUGACUUAUGUAUCUUAAACCAUCCCUACAUCCCUGGUAUGAAACUCACUUAAUUAUGGGUGGAUUAGCUUUUCGAUAUGCUGUGGGAUUCAGUUCUCUAGUAUUAUGUUGAGGAUUUUUGCAUCUAUGUUCAUCAGGGAUAUUGGUCUGUAGUCUGUAGUUUUCUUUUUUUGUUAUGUCUUUCACUGGUUUUGGUAUUAGGGUGACAGUGGCUCCACAGAAUGAUUUACAAAGGAUUCCCUCUUUAUCCUUUGGAAUAGUGUCAAUAGGAUUGGUAUUAAUUCUUCUUUGAAUGUCUGAUAGAAUUCAGCUGUGAAUCUGUCUGGUCCUGGACUUUUUUUUGGCAAUUUUUUUCAUUACAAUUUCAGUCAUGCUGCUUGUUACUGGUCUGAUCAGAGAUUCUAUAUCUUCCUUUUUUAAUCCAGGAGGGUUGUAUAGUUCCAGGAAUUUGGUUAUCUCUUCCAGGUUUUUUAGUUUAUCUGCACAAAGGUGUUCAUAGUAGCCUUGAUUAAUCAUUUGUAUUUCUAUGGAAUCAAUUGUAAUAUCUCCCUUUUCAUUUCUAAUUGUGUUUAUUUGCAUCUUCUCUAUUCUUUUUUGGUUAAUCUUGCUAAUGGUCUAUCAACUUUAUUCGUCUUUUUAAAGAACUAGCUUUUUGUUUCAUUUAUCUUUUGUAUUUUUUUUGUUUCAAUUUCAUUUAGUUCUGCUCUGAUCUUCAUUAUUUCUUUUCUUCUUCUGGGUUUGGGUUUGGAUUGUUCUUGUUUCUCCUGUUCUGUGAGGUGCGACCUAAGAUUAUCUCUUUGUGCUGUCUCAGACUUUUUGAUGUAGGCAUCUAAUGGAAUGAACUUUCCUCUUAGCACUGCUUUUGCUGUAUCCCAGAAGUUUUGCUAGGUUUUGUCACUAUUAUCAUCCAGUUCAAAGAAUUUUUAAAUUUCCCUCUUGAUUGCAAUGUUGUCCCAAUAAUCAUCCAGGAGCAGGUUAUUUAAUUUCCAUGUAUUUGCAAGGUUUUGAGGGUUCCUUUUGGAGUUGAUUUUCAAUUUUAUUCUACUGUGGUCUGAGACAGUACUUGAUAUAAUUUUGAUUUUCUUAAAUUCACUGAGACUUGUUUUUUGGCCUAUCAUAUGGUCUAUCUUGGAGAAUGUUCUGUGUACUGAUGAAUAGAAUAUAUACUCUGCAGUUGCUUAGUAGAAUGUUCUGUAAAUAUCUGUUAAUCCCAUUUCUUGUAGCAUAUAGUUUAAGUGCAUUGUUUCUUUUUUUACUUUCUGUCUUAAAGACCUGUCUAGUGCUCUCAGUGGAGUAUUGAAGUCCCCCACUAUUAUUGCAUUGUCAUCUAUCUCCUUUCUUAGGUCUAGUAGUAAUUGUUUUAUAAAUUUGAGAGUUCCACUGUUAUGUGCAAAUAUAUUUUGGAUUGUAAUAUUUUCCUGUUAGACUAGCCCUUUUAUCAUUACAAAAUGUCCCUCUUUGUCUUUUUUUAACUGCUCUUGCUUUAAAGUUUGUUUUUUUCUAAUAUAAGAAUAUCUAUUCCUGCUUGCUUUUGGUGUCAAUUUGCAUGGAAUAUGUUCUUUCACCCCUUUAACUUAAGUUUAUGUGAGUCCUUAUGUGUUUGGUGAGUUUCCUGAAGAUGCACAAACUUGGUUGGUGAAUUCUUAUCCAUUCUGCCAUUCUGUAUUUUUUAAGUGGAACAUUUAGGCCACUAACAUCAAUGUCGGAAUUGAGAUGUGAGGUACUAUUCUAUACAUCGUGCUAUUUGUUACCUGAAUAUCUGAAGUUUUUUUGUUUGUUUUCAUUAUGUUAUUGUUAUAUAGGUCCUGUAAUAUUUAUGCUUUAAGGAGGCUCUAUUUGGUGUAUUCCAAGAAUUUGUUUCAAGGUUUAGAGCUCCUUUCAGCAGUUCUUGUUGUGCAGGCUUGAUAGUGUUGAAUUCUCUCAGCAUUUGUUUGUCUGAAAAAGAUGGUGCCUUUCCUUCAUUUCUGAAGCAUAGCUUCGCUGGAUACAAAAUUCUUAGCUAAUAAUUAUUUUAUUUAAGGAGGCUGAUGAUAGGGCGCCAAUCCCUUCUAGCUUGUAGGGCUUCUGCUAAUAAAUCUGCUAAUAAAUCUGCUAUCAAUGUGAUAGGUUUUUCUUUACAGGUUACCUGAUGCUUUUCUCUCACGGCUGACAUUUUUUCCUUUGCCUUGACUUUAGAUAACUUGUUAUGUACCUAGGGAAUGAUCUUUUUGUCAUGAAUUUCCCAGGUGUUCUUUGAGCUUCUUGAGUUUGGAUGUUUAGAUCCAGCAAGGCUGGUAGUAAUUUUCCUCUAUUAUUCCUUCAAAUAUAUUUUCCAGACUUUUAGAUUUCUCUUCUUCCUCAAGAACACCAAUUAUUCUUAGGUCCGGACAUUUGACAUAGUAUCAAACUUCUUGGAGGCUUUGUUUUUAGGUUUUUUUUCUUGUCUUGAAUGAACUGGGUUAAUUUGAAAGCCUUGUCUUCAAGCUCCGAGGUUCUUUCUUCUGCUCGUUGGAUUUUAUUGGUGAGAAUUUCCAGUGCAUUUCACAUUUCUCUAAGUGUGUCCUUGAUUUUUAGAAGUUGUGAGUGUUUUUAUUUAUGCUGUUUAUUUCACUGAAGAAUUUUUCUUUUAUUUUCUGUAUCAUGAUUUUUAUUUCUUUACAUUAGACUUCACUUUUCUUUGGUGCCUCUUUGAUUAGCUUAAUAAUUGGCAAUACUUUUUCUGGCAAUUCAGAGAUUUCCUCUUCGUUUGGAUCCAUUGGUGGUGAACUGGUGUGAUCUUUUGGGGGUAUUACAGAACCUUGUUUUAUCAUAUUACAGAAUUUUUUUUUCUGGUUCCUUCUUAUUUGGGUAGACUAUGUCAGAGGGAAGACCUGGGAUUCAAGUUCUGCUGUUCAGUGUCUUUUGUCCCACUGAGUGCUCCCUCGAUGUGGUGUUCUCAUUCCCCUAGGAAUGAGGCUUCCUGAGAGCCAAACUGUAGUGGCUGUCUAGCCACACAGUGGAGCUACCAGGUUCCAUACUGGUACUUGGGAGUGUCUGCAAAGAUCCUGUAAUAUGAUCUGUCUUCAGGUCUUGCAGCCAUGGAUACCAGUUCCUGCUCCAGUCGAUGUAGCAGGGGAGUGAAAGGAACUCUGCUAGGGUCUUUGGUUGUGUUUUUGUUUAUUGUGCUGCUUGUUUUGUUGGCCUUCAGCCAGGAGGUAGUGCUUUCCAGAGUGCAUCAGCGGCCCUUAGGGAGGAUGCAAACUUGCCCUAGGGACACCUGGUCAAGUAUUCAGGUUUCUCAGGUGAUGGGUGAGGCCAUAGAGGUAACAAGAGAUUAUGACGUUUGUCUUCAGCUACCAAGGUGGAUAGAGAAAGACCACCAGGUCAGGGUAGGGAUGGCUGUGUCUGAGUUCAGCCUCUUCUUGGGUGGGGCUUGCUGCUGCUGCUGCUGUGGCAGAUGGGGGUGUGGUUUCCAGUCCAUUGGAGUUAUAUUCCUAGGGAGAUUAUGGCUGCCUCUGCUGCAACACAUAGGUCACCAGAAAAGUGGGAGAAAGCCGGCAGUCACCAGCUUCACUCAGCAUCCACACAGCCCACAGUCCUAAAGGCCAGUCGUGCUCCCACCGUGCCCACACAACAGCACCAAGUCUAUUUCCAGGCAGCUGGUGACCAGGGCUGAGAAUUUGCCCCAGACCAUGAGCCUCUCUGUUGAGAAAGCAAACAGACUCACAGGUUUUCAUUGUCUCAGGGAGCCUGCAGUGGUGAUCCAGUUCCUUCAAAGGAUCUGUGGAUUCUCUCAGCUUUCCUGGUAUGUUACUGCAGUAGUUCUUGGCACAAAAUUUCACAAUGUGAGUUUCCAUACGGUAUUCUGUGUCAGGCCUCUGAGCCCAAGUUAAGCCAUCAUAUCCCUUGUGACCUGCACGUAUACAUCCAGAUGGCCUGAAGCAACUGAAGAUCCACAAAAGAAGUGAAAAUAGCCUUAACUGAUGACAUUCCACCAUUGUGAUUUGUUUCUGCCCCACCCUAACUGAUCAGUGUACUUUGUAAUGUCCCCCACCCUUAAGAAGGUUCUUUGUAAUCUCCCCCACCCUUAAGAAGGUUCUUUGUAAUCUCCCCAACUCUUAAGAAGGUUCUUUGUAAUUCUCCCCACCCUUGAGAGUGUACUUUGUGAGAUCCACCACCUGCCCCCAAAACAUUGCUCCUAACUCCACUGCCUAUCCCAAAACCUGUAAGAACUAAUGAUAAUCCCACCACACUUUGCUGAUUCUCUUUUCGGACUCAGCCCACCUGCACCCAGGUGAAAUAAACAGCCUUGUUGCUCACACAAAGCCUGUUUGGUGGUCUCUUCACAUGGACACUUGAGACACUCUGUCCAUCUGAGUGGGAGCUGCAAGCUAGUCCUGCCUCCUAUCCACCAUCUUAAUCCUAGUCAGGACAUUAAAGUUUUCUGUUUAUUCAGUAUCAUAAAUGUUGAAGUAUGCACCAAGGUAGCAAACAAAUCUUCUUUUCCCAGGGUAUAAACUCAAAAUUUUAUUGAGACUCUUGAAACUCACUUUGGAGUAAAAGUUAAUACACUGGACUUUUACAUUUUUAGUCUGUAUUUUAUAGUCAUUUUUAUUUUGGGGGGACUCUUGGAGAUGCUGCUGUGACUUCAACCCAGGUGACAUCUUAACAUUUGAUCUCUAAUUACUUCCAUCACAAAAAGUUAACUUUUAUUAUGGGAUCCCAGAUCCAAAUUUCUUUCAAGUUGUUAAAAUUCAUCUAAGCUUCACACACUGAUCCAACAGAGAAAUUGUUUCAUUAUUUAAAUUCUCAGUGGAUAGAUAAUUUACAUGUGCCCCUAAACUGCACAAUGAUACUUAAACAUUUUAUUAAUAAUUACAGGACUUAUAUUGAAAUUUAGAAUAUAAGUAAAUGUUUCUGAAUUUUCAAAUGUAAGUAUAUUUUUACAUAAUAGUAAUUUUUUUUUUUUUUUAAUUACAGAGUCUCGCUCUGGGGCCCAGGCUGGAGUGCGGUGGUGCGAUCUUGGCUCACUGCAACCUCCUCCUUCCGGGUUCAAGCAAUUCUCCCUGCCUCAGCCUCCCAAGUAGCUGAGACUACAGGGGCCUGCUAAUCUCUCAGGGCCCAUGCGAAAUCUAUCUCAAUCAAAAGUGCAUUAUUCUUAGAAGCAGAUAUUACAAAAUUUAAUUUCCUAAUUUGGCCAAGUGGCAUGGGCUGAGCUAAUUUUUGUAUUUUUCAGUAGAGAUGGGGUUUUGCCAUAAAAUAAAAUUGUAAUAACUCUAUUGCUGUCACAUUCCCUAUAAGGAAAAUCAUUUAAUCUUAGUUGCACAGGCUUUAUUUAUAUUAUUGAUUCACAAGAGAAUCAAAUUUUUCUAAAAUUGGUCAAUUGUUUUAGCAUUUCUGCUCUUUGAAUAGGAUUAGAGUUUAUGGAACAAUGUAAAAUCCUAUAAUAUAUUUCCAGUCUUUGAAGUCCUUUUAAAGAAAAUCAUGUCCAGCAUAUAGAUUAAGUGGUCAAAUAGAUAUUUCCACAGUGGCUCAAAGUAAUACAUAAAGAGAAUAACAUUUAGACUUUAUUACAUGACUACAGUACAUGUGCCUUACCUUGAAAUAAAUAGUGAAACUGUACAUGAAACAAGAAGUAUACUAAUAGCCAUCAAAUAUUUUAAAUAUUAAUUCAUAAUGCUAUACAUUAAUGACUCUAGAAUAUGCAUCACAACCAUUUAUAUAUUAGGUAGAAAGAAAGAAAGAAAAUAUUCAAUAAUCCUUAUCUUUUUAACAAUUAAGCAAAAUGCAUAAUUAAUUAUAGUUAUCUUAAAUCACUUGGCCAAAUAAGGAAAAUAAAUUUUGUAAAACCUGCUUCUAAAUAUAAUGUACUUUUUAUUAAGAUAGAUUCAUUUAUAUCCACAGAUCUAUGGUUAUACUGAAGUAUAGAUAAUUUAAUUCAGGCCAAAAACUGAUUUUUAAAAACUCAUAUGGUUUCUAAAUUAUCCAAAUUAUUUUCUAACUUAGUUUUUUUUUCUUUUUCUUGGUCUGGUAUUAAAGAAGCAUUUUCCAAAAGUUAUUGUUUUAUAAUUUUAAACAUAAUUUUUUUCUAAGUUAAUUGAAAUUACUGAUAAGGAAAAUGAAUAAAGACACUAUUUAAAUUUAUGCUGGCUAUGAAAAACAGAAACCAGGCUCCUGUCUUUGUUUCCAGUCUCACCUACUUUCAGCAGACAGGACAAUAUUUAUUCUACAGAGUGUUGUUUUACAACAUCCUAUGUGAACUCAUUUCUCUUUUGAACUCACUGUUACUAAUAAUUUAACAUGUUUUUACAUCAUUUUGUUUUAUUCAUAUUAUAAAGGAUUAUAUAUCUGUUGUGG